GGAAAGAAGUGGAAUAAUUAGGAACCUAGGGUGGGGUAGGGUAGCAGGACAUUUCAAACAUUAAUGAGCAUAUGAGAUUCCAGGUCUUGUUAAAAUGCAAAUUCUGAUUCAGCUGGUAGGUGAGGUCUGAGAUUGUGCAUUUCUAACAAGCACUCAGAUAAUCUUAAGGCUGUUGGCCCCAGGGUCACACUUAUAGUGAUUUUCUAGAACCCAGUUGGGGAAGUGAAUCUUGGGCAGGAGAAAUACACACCUCUUGCAUUGAGUUUGGAGAUCUCAUCUGAUAUAACUUUUUAAGAAAGAAAAAUAAUUUUCCAAAUAUCCAAUUGAUAAGCUUUCCCACUAAGUGGCUUUCCCACUAAGUGGCUGCGUUAUGAAAAUUGCUUCACUUUGAAACUUCUGGUCUUGGUAAUAUAGAAUUUCUGUGUUCUCACAGUGCUUGAUUGAGAAUAUGAUAUUGAGAUUAUGGCAUAAAAUAUAGUGGCUGUACAAAAAAAAAUACAUUAUUAGGAUCUCUAACAAUUAUGUAAAAGUCAUUGCUUCAUGGGUAGAGCUCAAACUUUGGUGUGAGACCUGGUUUUAUUCUUGGCACUUACUCUGAGUUGUCUUAGGCAAAUUAAUACCUUAAGCAAAAAUAUUCUCAUGUACAUUUUACAUGAGAAUUAUAAAUGAAGUACAUAAAGUCCAGCAGUCACAAAUGUUAUCUAUUAUUACCAUCGUCCUAAGACUGCAAUCAGCUAUAGUGAAAGUAGUCUCAAAGAUUGUUUCAUAAAUCAUCAGAUUCACCUAAUUUUCUAAAGAAUUUAAAUAAGGAGAUGGAAUGAAUAGAUUGCAUUUUGUUUCCAUGCACAGGGGAACUGUGCAUAUUUCUUCUGUGACUCGGAAAUGGUUUAACUUUUAAAAAUCCCAAAAUAGCUGAAGUUAGCAGACAUGCAAUUUACCAAGGAUGAUUGGAAUUUUUAUCUUUCCUGUAAUAAUACUAUACCCAAGCACACUGCUCAUGAGGAAAACAUUUUUAUGUGAAUCUUUUACUCUUGGGGGCAAAGAAUGCUGUUUUUCUUUUUGAUAACUAUGUUUAUAGAAUCUAAAUCACCCUGAGCAAUUAUUUCAACAUCUAAAGUUAUUAUUACCAUUCAUGUUUCAUUUAUAGCUAUUUGAAUUUUGAUGAAUUUCAAUAUGGUGCUACAGUGAUAGGGCAAGUGCAAAUAAGUUCAAUAUAUGGGUACGGUCUAAAGCUAUUUUAAUUUUUUUAUUACAACUGCUAUGAAGAAAAUUAGGAUAUGCCAUAUUUUCACGUUUUACAGUUGGAUGUCCUAUGAUGUUCUCUUCCAGAGAACAGAGCUCGGAGCUCUGGAAAUUUGGAGGCAACUGAUAUGUGCUCAUGUCUGCAUCUGUGUGGGUUGGCUGUAUCUCAGGGACAGAGUCUGCAGCAAAAAAGAUAUAAUUUUGAGGACUGAACAAAAUUCAGGAAGGACUAUUCUCAUUAAGGCAGUAACAGAGAAGAAUUUUGAAACAAAAGAUUUUCGAGCCUCUCUAGAAAAUGGUGUUCUGCUGUGUGAUUUGAUUAAUAAGCUUAAACCUGGCGUCAUUAAGAAGAUCAAUAGACUGUCUACACCAAUAGCAGGAUUGGAUAAUAUAAACGUUUUCUUGAAAGCUUGUGAACAGAUUGGAUUGAAAGAAGCCCAGCUUUUCCAUCCUGGAGAUCUACAGGAUUUAUCAAAUCGAGUCACUGUCAAGCAAGAAGAGACUGACAGGAGAGUGAAAAAUGUUUUGAUAACAUUGUACUGGCUGGGAAGAAAAGCACAAAGCAACCCGUACUAUAAUGGUCCCCAUCUUAAUUUGAAAGCGUUUGAGAAUCUUUUAGGACAAGCACUGACGAAGGCACUCGAAGACUCCAGCUUCCUGAAAAGAAGUGGCAGGGACAGUGGCUACGGUGACAUCUGGUGUCCUGAACGUGGAGAAUUUCUUGCUCCUCCAAGGCACCAUAAGAGAGAAGAUUCCUUUGAAAGCUUGGACUCUUUGGGCUCGAGGUCAUUGACAAGCUGCUCCUCUGAUAUCACGUUGAGAGGGGGGCGUGAAGGUUUUGAAAGUGACACAGAUUCGGAAUUUACAUUUAAGAUGCAGGAUUAUAAUAAAGAUGAUAUGUCGUAUCGAAGGAUUUCGGCUGUUGAGCCAAAGACUGCGUUACCCUUCAAUCGUUUUUUACCCAACAAAAGUAGACAGCCAUCCUAUGUACCAGCACCUCUGAGAAAGAAAAAGCCAGACAAACAUGAGGAUAACAGAAGAAGUUGGGCAAGCCCGGUUUAUACAGAAGCAGAUGGAACAUUUUCAAGACUCUUUCAAAAGAUUUAUGGUGAGAAUGGGAGUAAGUCCAUGAGUGAUGUCAGCGCAGAAGAUGUUCAAAACUUGCGUCAGCUGCGUUACGAGGAGAUGCAGAAAAUAAAAUCACAAUUAAAAGAACAAGAUCAGAAAUGGCAGGAUGACCUUGCAAAAUGGAAAGAUCGUCGAAAAAGUUACACUUCAGAUCUGCAGAAGAAAAAAGAAGAGAGAGAAGAAAUUGAAAAGCAGGCACUUGAGAAGUCUAAGAGAAGCUCUAAGACGUUUAAGGAAAUGCUGCAGGACAGGGAAUCCCAAAAUCAAAAGUCUACAGUUCCGUCAAGAAGGAGAAUGUAUUCUUUUGAUGAUGUGCUGGAGGAAGGAAAGCGACCCCCUACAAUGACUGUGUCAGAAGCAAGUUACCAGAGUGAGAGAGUAGAAGAGAAGGGAGCAACUUAUCCUUCAGAAAUUCCCAAAGAAGAUUCUACCACUUUUGCAAAAAGAGAGGACCGUGUAACAACUGAAAUUCAGCUUCCUUCUCAAAGUCCUGUGGAAGAACAAAGCCCAGCCUCUUUGUCUUCUCUGCGUUCACGGAGCACACAAAUGGAAUCAACUCGUGUUUCAGCUUCUCUCCCCAGAAGUUACCGGAAAACUGAUACAGUCAGGUUAACAUCUGUGGUCACACCAAGACCCUUUGGCUCUCAGACAAGGGGAAUCUCAUCACUCCCCAGAUCUUACACGAUGGAUGAUGCUUGGAAGUAUAAUGGAGAUGUUGAAGACAUUAAGAGAACUCCAAACAAUGUGGUCAGCACCCCUGCACCAAGCCCGGACGCAAGCCAACUGGCUUCAAGCUUAUCUAGCCAGAAAGAGGUAGCAGCAACAGAAGAAGAUGUGACAAGGCUGCCCUCUCCUACAUCCCCCUUCUCAUCUCUUUCCCAAGACCAGGCUGCCACUUCUAAAGCCACAUUGUCUUCCACAUCUGGUCUUGAUUUAAUGUCUGAAUCUGGAGAAGGGGAAAUCUCCCCACAAAGAGAAGUCUCAAGAUCCCAGGAUCAGUUCAGUGAUAUGAGAAUCAGCAUAAACCAGACGCCUGGGAAGAGUCUUGACUUUGGGUUUACAAUAAAAUGGGAUAUUCCUGGGAUCUUCGUAGCAUCAGUUGAAGCAGGUAGCCCAGCAGAAUUUUCUCAGCUACAAGUAGAUGAUGAAAUUAUUGCUAUUAACAACACCAAGUUUUCAUAUAACGAUUCAAAAGAGUGGGAGGAAGCCAUGGCUAAGGCUCAAGAAACUGGACACCUAGUGAUGGAUGUGAGGCGCUAUGGAAAGGCUGGUUCACCUGAAACAAAGUGGAUUGAUGCAACUUCUGGAAUUUACAACUCAGAAAAAUCUUCAAAUCUAUCUGUAACAACUGAUUUCUCCGAAAGCCUUCAGAGUUCUAAUAUUGAAUCCAAAGAAAUCAAUGGAAUUCAUGAUGAAAGCAAUGCUUUUGAAUCAAAAGCAUCUGAAUCCAUUUCUUUGAAAAACUUAAAAAGGCGAUCACAAUUUUUUGAACAAGGAAGCUCUGAUUCGGUGGUUCCUGAUCUUCCAGUUCCAACCAUCAGUGCCCCGAGUCGCUGGGUGUGGGAUCAAGAGGAGGAGCGGAAGCGGCAGGAGAGGUGGCAGAAGGAGCAGGACCGCCUACUGCAGGAAAAAUAUCAACGUGAGCAGGAGAAACUGAGGGAAGAGUGGCAAAGGGCCAAACAGGAGGCAGAGAGAGAGAAUUCCAAGUACUUGGAUGAGGAACUGAUGGUCCUAAGCUCAAACAGCAUGUCUCUGACCACACGGGAGCCCUCUCUUGCCACCUGGGAAGCUACCUGGAGUGAAGGGUCCAAGUCUUCAGACAGAGAAGGAACCCGAGCAGGAGAAGAGGAGAGGAGACAGCCACAAGAGGAAGUUGUUCAUGAGGACCAAGGAAAGAAGCCGCAGGAUCAGCUUGUUAUUGAGAGAGAGAGGAAAUGGGAGCAACAGCUUCAGGAAGAGCAAGAGCAAAAGCGGCUUCAGGCUGAGGCUGAGGAGCAGAAGCGUCCUGCGGAGGAGCAGAAGCGCCAGGCAGAGAUAGAGCGGGAAACAUCAGUCAGAAUAUACCAGUACAGGAGGCCUGUUGAUUCCUAUGAUAUACCAAAGACAGAAGAAGCAUCUUCAGGUUUUCUUCCUGGUGACAGGAAUAAAUCCAGAUCUACUACUGAACUGGAUGAUUACUCCACAAAUAAAAAUGGAAACAAUAAAUAUUUAGACCAAAUUGGGAACAUGACCUCUUCACAGAGGAGAUCCAAGAAAGAACAAGUACCAUCAGGAGCAGAAUUGGAGAGGCAACAAAUCCUUCAGGAAAUGAGGAAGAGAACACCCCUUCACAAUGACAACAGCUGGAUCCGACAGCGCAGUGCCAGUGUCAACAAAGAGCCUGUUAGUCUUCCUGGGAUCAUGAGAAGAGGCGAAUCUUUAGAUAACCUGGACUCCCCCCGAUCCAAUUCUUGGAGACAGCCUCCUUGGCUCAAUCAGCCCACAGGAUUCUAUGCUUCUUCCUCUGUGCAAGACUUUAGUCGCCCACCACCUCAGCUGGUGUCCACAUCAAACCGUGCCUACAUGCGGAACCCCUCCUCCAGCGUGCCCCCACCUUCAGCUGGCUCCGUGAAGACCUCCACCACAGGUGUGGCCACCACACAGUCCCCCACCCCGAGAAGCCAUUCCCCUUCAGCUUCACAGUCAGGCUCUCAGCUGCGUAACAGGUCAGUCAGUGGGAAGCGCAUAUGCUCCUACUGCAAUAACAUUCUGGGCAAAGGAGCCGCCAUGAUCAUCGAGUCCCUGGGUCUUUGUUAUCAUUUGCAUUGUUUUAAGUGUGUUGCCUGUGAGUGUGACCUCGGAGGCUCUUCCUCAGGAGCUGAAGUCAGGAUCAGAAACCACCAACUGUACUGCAACGACUGCUAUCUCAGAUUCAAAUCUGGACGGCCAACCGCCAUGUGAUGUAAGCCUCCAUACGAAAGCACUGUUGCAGAUAGAAGAAGAGGUGGUUGCUGCUCAUGUAGAUCUAUAAAUAUGUGUUGUAUGUCUUUUUUGCUUUUUUUUUAAAAAAAAGAAUAACUUUUUUUGCCUCUUUAGAUUACAUAGAAGCAUUGUAGUCUUGGUAGAACCAGUAUUUUUGUUGUUUAUUUAUAAGGUAAUUGUGUGUGGGGAAAAGUGCAGUAUUUACCUGUUGAAUUCAGCAUCUUGAGAGCACAAGGGAAAAAAUAAGAACCUACGAAUAUUUUUGAGGCAGAUAAUGAUCUAGUUUGACUUUCUAGUUAGUGGUGUUUUGAAGAGGGUAUUUUAUUGUUUUUUAAAAAAAGGUUCUUAAACAUUAUUUGAAAUAGUUAAUAUAAAUACAUAAUUGCAUUUGCUCUGUUUAUUGUAAUGUAUUCUAAAUUAAUGCAGAACCAUAUGGAAAAUUUCAUUAAAAUCUAUCCCCAAAUGUGCUUUCUGUAUCCUUCCUUCUACCUAUUAUUCUGAUUUUUAAAAAUGCAGUUAAUGUACCAUUUAUUUGCUUGAUGAAGGGAGCUCUAUUUUCUUUACCAGAAAUGUUGCUAAGUAAUUCCCAAUAGAAAGCUGCUUAUUUUCAUUAAUGAAAAAUAACCAUGGUUUGUAUACUAGAAGUCUUCUUCAGAAACUGGUGAGCCUUUCUGUUCAAUUGCAUUUGUAAAUAAACUUGCUGAUGCAUUUAACGAGUGGGUCGUCUUUUUCUUAGGUGUAUGUGUCUGACCUCAGGCCUUUUAGCCAUAUUUCAGUAUGUGGCCUUUUUUGAUGUUAUGUUUUAUCCAGUAGCUUUACUAAGGUAUAAUUGAUGUAAUAAACUGCAUAUAUUUAAAGUGUAUACUUUGACAAAUUUUGACAUGGUGUAUACCUUCGAAACUAUGCCACAGUCUGGAUGUGUUUACUGAAACAUUUUAAUAAGGAAGUUUAUUUUUGAUAAAGUUAUGUUUUUGGAUACAAUAUAUUUGUAUGGUGAGAGUGAUGAAUUGUUGGAUCAUUUGAAUAAAAUCUUUUACUAACCCCAUGAUAAAAGGAGAAGACAACAGUGAGCUUAGAAUAUCUAUAAAGCAAAAAAUGUAGUCUCUUGUUUAAAAAAUCUGGAGCGGGAAUGCAAGGAUACAAAACUUUAGCAUGCUUUGAGCAAAAAUUUAAACUUACUGGAAUCUUUUAUAAUAAUGUAAGUGGAAUGGAGGAUUCUAGGAACUGAGAACUGUAUUGGAAUAGGUUCAAAAUAUGUAAGAAAUGCUAAUGUGGGAGAUAAAAAUUUUAUUUAGUACUUAUUCUGAUUAUUAUUAAAGUAAUAAUGUGUUCCUUGAGGAUAACUUGUCAAAUGCCCCAAAGCAUAAAGAAUAUAAUUCUGAAUCCCAAAUUCCAAAGACAAGAACUCUGUGUUUGAAUUCAUUCUGCAUAUAAUUAUUUAUAAGUAUAGAUUGUGAAUUUUUCCAUGUUCUUAAAAUUAUUUUUAUCUUUUUUCAUGGUUGCAUAGUGCUCCAUUGUUUGGCCUUGGUAAUAUUUAGUUGAUAAUUCCAUUACUGUGUAUUUUUCACUUGUUUCUAAGAUCAAACAUUUUAAUAUGUGCAUGUUAUAUAUAAAUAUGUAAAUUCUGUGAUACUCUAUGAUCAUCUCUUUCUUUAUAUUAUUUUCAUAGACAUGAAAUAGUUGCUCAGAGAUUAUGCAUUUUAAGACACUCAUAGUAUAUAUUGCCAAAGUGGUUUCCAGAAAGGCACUGCUGGCUUCGACUCCUAUAAGCAGCACGUGGGCUUGUUCAUCUCACUGCAUGUUUAUGAAGAUACAGUUCUUUUGCCUUGUUCUCUGCCUGAUGUGUAUGCAGAGGCAGCCCUCAAUAUGCAGUGGUUGAAUAAAUGAAUGAAGAAACCACUAUCAA